AGGAGGAGCACCCCGCAGGCUGAGGGCAGGUGGGAAGCAAACCCGGACGCAUCGCAGCAGCAGCAGCAGCAGCAGAAGCAGCAGCAGCAGCCUCCGCAGUCCCUCCAGAGACAUGGAUCCCCAGACAGCACCUUCCCGGGCGCUCCUGCUCCUGCUCUUCUUGCAUCUGGCUUUCCUGGGAGGUCGUUCCCACCCGCUGGGCAGCCCCGGUUCAGCCUCGGACUUGGAAACGUCCGGGUUACAGGAGCAGCGCAACCAUUUGCAGGGCAAACUGUCGGAGCUGCAGGUGGAGCAGACAUCCCUGGAGCCCCUCCAGGAGAGCCCCCGUCCCACAGGUGUCUGGAAGUCCCGGGAGGUAGCCACCGAGGGCAUCCGUGGGCACCGCAAAAUGGUCCUCUACACCCUGCGGGCACCACGAAGCCCCAAGAUGGUGCAAGGGUCUGGCUGCUUUGGGAGGAAGAUGGACCGGAUCAGCUCCUCCAGUGGCCUGGGCUGCAAAGUGCUGAGGCGGCAUUAAGAGGAAGUCCUGGCUGCAGACACCUGCUUCUGAUUCCACAAGGGGCUUUUUCCUCAACCCUGUGGCCGCCUUUGAAGUGACUCAUUUUUUUAAUGUAUUUAUGUAUUUAUUUGAUUGUUUUAUAUAAGAUGGUUUCUUACCUUUGAGCACAAAAUUUCCACGGUGAAAUAAAGUCAACAUUAUAAGCUUUA